CUAAAGUUUGUUCUGAGAUAAUUUAAUUGCAUGUCUAAAAUCCAGAGAGUGAUGAUGAAUCUCAAGGCCUUUGUGCCUUCUGUGAGGCUACACGGCAUGUGAUUUCUUUUGGUGGCAGUCAGAAGGGGAUGACGUGGUCUGGCCACUGGAAUAUGAAGGGGAGUUGCCCAAAUAGCAUUUCCCUCUUUGGUAGGGCUCUUACCUGGCAGGAGACUCAUGCCAGUCGGAUCUGGUGUUAAGGAGGGUUUGCUCCGGAGAGUUUAGCCAGUGAUUAGGUUCUUUUUGAUAUCUCCCUCUCUUUCUUCCUUUCUGUUGUCCUGCUGUCCCCGUGUCAGGCCUGUGUUGUUGUUAUAGCCUCCCUUUCCCUCCUGCUUCCUUUGGCCCUUCUGAUCCAGUCUGUAUGCAGCUACCAGGUCAUUCUUCCUAAAACACCCCUUCCCGGUGUCACUCCCUUUCUCACAGACUUGCAAUGGCUCCCCGUUCCCUGCAGUCUGACCCUAGACAGUGUCCCCUCCAGCUCUUCCCUAGCCAUACCAUGCACAUUUUUUCUUCCUGCAUCUUCACUGCUGCCGCUCCCCUUCCUUUACUCCCACUUGAAUCCCACUUGUCCUUAGUCUGGUUGUUGCUCAGACCACUCCAGGCCAACAUAGUCAUCCCCGCCUGAGCUCAUGACUCUGGAUUUUCUAACGUGGUAUCCUCUUGAGUGGUUUUGUAGGUUGGAAAUUUCUUAAGGACAGGAACAAUAUGAGUGUUAAACCUCUGUGUGUGUGUGUGUGUGUGUGAAUAUUCUGGUAUUUCUUGUACAGUGCUGUGCACAUCAUUUUUGUUGAGUGAAUAAAUGUGGUUGGUUGCUGAGUUAGGCAGGAACAAGGGGGAGACCUUCCUUUCAGCUUCUCCAGAAAUGCUCAUAUUGGAGUCCUUGGAGAUUUCCAGCCCUUUCUGUCAAAGGCAUAUGGAUAGGGCAUGUUUGGGGUGCUGUAAAUGGGAAAUUUAACUGCUGUUUCUAAUAUUUCUGCUGGUGAAGAGUCCUAUGGAUUGCUUAUGUGAUACCAUAUAGACAUUGGAAAAGGGCUGUAAUCCUGUUUUCCUCCUACCUCACCGGACCACCAUUCUUUCUACCCAGCUUUGCUGCUCUUAUGCAGUUUUCCUUGUUGUUCAUGCUAAAUGAAUCCAUGUUUUAUCUCUUCUCAAACCGGGUGCAAAUGAGGGAGAAAACACAAUUCUGAGCACAGAAAAGAAAAAUACUCCUGGGUCUGGCCCAUAGAUGGGACUUUUGGGGCUGGUUUGGAAGAGGUGUUUAUGGGGGCAUCACCAACAUAAGAGGCACAAUCAGCCCCACAUUGGACCCCUCAUAAAGGAAAGCUACAAUCCCUGCUCUCUCAGGCUUCUGUUUUGGUUCACCAUCAACCCUGGACCAUGGGGGAAACGGGAAAGAGGACUGGUGACUGGUUAGAGGCCAGAUAGUGAAAAAAUAUAUUCUGCAUCCAUCCCCUUUCCCCCAAACCUCCCUUUUGUGCCCCAGUUUGAUGAUUAAUGGACCAGCAUUUCCCUUCUACGCGGGAAGGCCACCCCUCACAGUUGCCAUGGCAAUGCAGACCGCUCCCCCGUCAAUUAAAAAAAAAAUCCCUACUACUUCUCUCCUCCUUCUACUGUAGCAGGAGAAAAGCUACCUCAGAAUGCAUCUCCUGGGCUCUCUUCUCAGCUCCUUUAGCUGUGUUUGCUGUGUGUCCUAGAACACAGUCCUUCCUCUCUUUCUGGGGAUUGCCUGAGUUUCUUCACUCUGAGCAAAUUGUGCCCCUUCUGGAGCCAGCAGCCCCUGGAACACUUAUAUCAAGAAACAGAGAAAAUUUCUGUUUAUUUAUUCAUCCCCGGUGCAAAUUAAAAACUAGAGAGAGCUCCUUUUGGGUAAAAAAAAAAAAAAAAAAAACAACCCUUUCACACCUUCUCUGGUUAGAGGUAUAAGUUGGGGCACAUUUGACAUCCAGAAAGGAAGUUUUAGUAAACCUGGAAGGAAUUCAGCCUCCUAGCAUACAUACUUCAAAUUGGAGUUCUAUGGGGAAUUCUCAAAAUUAUUUUCAUUCCUCCUCACCUCUCUGUUCCAGCAUCCAGGAGGACUUGUGUGUUUUCAUUUUAUCUGUUCUUAUUCCUCUUGGCCUUGCUCCGGCAACAUCUGGCCUCAGCACCCUGUCGCAAGGUUGGAAGUACUCCAUGACACACACUCGGAGAAAGUCCCUUCCCAUGCUGAGUUCGGGCCUCACUGGCCGCCGAGAGCCCCUGCAGAUGGAAGACAGCAACAUGGAGCAGGGGGUUGAGGGUGUGGAGCCAGGCAUGCCCGAGAGCCCAGGUCACCUCACAGGGCGCCGCAAGAAUUACCCACUUCGUAAGCGCCCAUUGGUUCCUGAGAAGCCCAAGGCCUGCAAAGUGCUGCUGACUCGCCUGGAGAAUGUGGCCGGUCCCCGGAGUGCAGAUGAGGCUGAUGAGCUACCGCCUGACCUGCCCAAGCCCCCCAGCCCGGCCCCAUCCAGUGAAGACCCUGGCCUUGCCCAGCCCCGCAAGCGGCGCCUGGCCUCCCUCAAUGCUGAAGCUCUCAAUAACCUGCUGCUGGAGCGAGAGGACACCAGCAGCCUGGCAGGCACCCGCCGCAGUCGAGCAGGGGAUCCCCACCGCAGCCGUGACCGUGAUCGUGCUACUGGGGGCUGGUCCUCCUCCAAGAAGCGGCCCCGGCUGGGGGACCUUGGAGGAGGAAGUCGGGACCUGUCUCCAGAGCCAGCACCCGAUGAAGGUCCCCGCCGAGAUGGAGACCCAGCUCCCAAGAGACUGGCUAGCCUGAACGCAGCUGCUUUCCUAAAACUGAGCCAGGAGCGGGAGCUACCCCUGCGGCUGCCUCGUGCCCAUGCAGAAGUAGAUGGGCGCUCCACUGAGCCCCCAGCACCCAAGGCCCCGAGGCCAAAGUGGCCCAAGGUCAAUGGCAAGAACUAUCCCAAGGCUUGGCAGGGGGCCAGCUCUGGGGAGGCUGCAGGCCCACCUGGCUGGCAAGGCUGCCCUGAUGAACCAUGGCCAUCUGCAACUCCUUGUGGGCCAUCCGUCCAGCCAUCUCAUCAGCCCCUGAGCAAGGCUCUGGAGAGCCCUUUGGGGCUGCGCCCUCACCUGCCCCUGCUGAUGGGUGGACAGGCGGCUCUGAAGCCGGAGCCUGGGCGCCCAGGCGAGGAGUCACCUGCCCCUAAGCAGGAACUGCAUCAGCCCUCUUUCCCCACACCUCAGCUGUCGCCGCUGCCGAUGCCUGGCAACCCCGCCGACUACAAUGGCCUGUGUGUUGGGCCUGAGCUCACUGCACUAGGCAGCUUCUACCUGUACUGUGGCCAAGAGGGGCUGCAGUGUGGGGGCUACUCGCCCUGCCCCAUGCUUCCUGAGGGCAAGCUGUCCCCAGUGGCUGCACCUCACGAGGAGGGGCUCCUCUUAGCUCCGAGCUCAGUGCCCUCAGGCACCCCUUUCCAGCACCCUCCCUGGGGCUCCUCUCGCUACUGCUCUAGCGAGGACACUGGAGUGAAUGGCUACAGCAUCUGCGGAGUGUUGCCCCUGUCUGUUACCCACGCUGGCACUACCUGUGGCGGCUGCCCAUACAAAAUGCCUUUUGCAGCAGAAGGCUGCAGAUCCCUGGGCCAGUUGGAAUUUCCUCUCCCGGAAGCUGGCCACCCAGCCUCACCCGCCCACCCACUCCUGGGGUGCCCUGUACCCAGUGUGCCACCUGCAGCAGAGCCCGUCCCCCAUCUUCAGACACCCACCUCGGAGCCCCAGACAGUAGCCCGUGCGUGCCCUCAGAGCGCCAAACCUCCCAGCGGUUCUAAGUCAGGUCUGCGCACAGGCUCCAGCUGCAGGCACACUGCAAGGAGCAAGGCUGCCCGCAGGCCUAGCCACCCCAAGCAGCCACGUGUCCAGCGCCCACGCCCUCGCCGCCGCCGUCGCCGCCGCACUAAUGGCUGGGUACCUGUUGGGGCUGCGUGUGAGAAGGCUGUGUAUGUCUUGGAUGAGCCGGAGCCAGCCAUCCGAAAGAGCUACCAGGCGGUAGAGCGGCAUGGGGAGACAAUCCGAGUCCGGGACACCGUCCUUCUCAAAUCAGGCCCACGAAAGACCUCCACACCUUAUGUGGCCAAGAUCUCUGCCCUCUGGGAGAACCCCGAGUCAGGAGAGCUGAUGAUGAGCCUCCUGUGGUAUUACAGACCUGAGCACUUACAGGGAGGCCGCAGUCCCAGCAUGCACGAGCCCUUGCAGAAUGAAGUGUUUGCAUCGCGACAUCAGGACCAGAACAGUGUGGCCUGCAUUGAGGAGAAGUGCUAUGUGCUGACUUUUGCCGAGUACUGCAGGUUCUGUGCCAUGGCCAAGCGCCGAGGUGAAGGCCUCCCCAGCCGAAAGACAGCACUGGUUCCCCCCUCUGCAGACUAUUCCACCCCACCCCACCGCACAGUGCCAGAGGACACGGACCCUGAGCUGGUGUUCCUUUGCCGCCAUGUCUAUGACUUCCGCCACGGGCGCAUCCUUAAGAACCCCCAGUAGCCUCCUCAUGCCCAUGCUGGGGCUACCCAUGGGCAAGUGGGGCUCGGGGUAGGGGGCACUGCUUGAAGCACAGCACUUGGUUAGGGGGCCACAGAGGCCUAAGUUUGCUGGCCUGUGGUUUUCUUGGGGGGGAGGGCAGGGGCCCCUGUGGGUUCUGGGCUCCAGGGGAGGGAGCUGGGGAGGCCAGGGUAUAAGAAAAGCAUCAGAACUCUCAGCUUGGCCCAAGGUACCUUCUGUGGUUCCCCUGGGUGGAGAUUUCCGAAAAGUAGUCUUCUCUGAGGCUGGGCCAAGCCUGAGGGAAAUGGGGCCCUAGGAGGGUGGGGGCGGGAAGGAGGGGCAAGGUCUUUCAGGAACCAGACCCAACAGGCCCUUCUGUAGCCUCCCCCUUGCCCUCAAAGGGGGAGUGGGGGCCAGCUUUACCUCACCCACUGUGACCCGCCGCUUCCCCUUCAGCCUGGGACCAGGCUUUCCUAGAUCCCAGCACAGCUCUGAGCUUGUUCCUUUGAGGCAUAGAGAGCCAGAGUCUGGCUUCCAGAGCAUUGACUUCCUCUUCCUAGACUUGAGGCCUUUUCUCUGGCUUUCCUCCUUUGCCCUGCAGUAGCAACUGGUGCUGGGACAAGUUGACCCACCUCUCACAGUCAUGGGUGUGGCCCACUUGUGGGAGUCUCCUGUCCACCUCCCAGAGACGGCCACCCAGCGGGUCUGGCUUCCCAGAAAGUUAACUGAUGAUUGUGGGGUUUGUCAUAUCUGGGAGGGAAGAUGGGUGCUGGGAGAGGGUUGGGGGCAGGGGGCAAGGAAAAUUGCUACCUGAUUUGUUGAAGAUUUUUCCUCUUGCCUUACACAUGGAGGUUCCAGGAAACCUCUUGCAGAACUUCACACGUGAUUCUUCAAGCCACACCCACCUGAAAUCAAACCAAAGGAGUGCUGUGGCUCCCCUUGCCCUGCCACCCUUUCCCUAGUCUUUUGUAGAUUGCACUAAUUUACAUCCUAGCAAGAAUCAACACUGUAUCAGUCCACGGACCUGCUGAGCUGCAGCCACUUGCUCUAGGAGCUAAGGACUUGCAUUUUCAGUUUGUUCCUGUUGCCCAGAGGCCCUGUUCUCACCUCAUGCUGCUCCCCAGAGUAGACUAACAGGCUCAGUCCCCUGUUGUCCUUGUGGAGACUAGGCCUUGGCCCUGGCCCUGAGACUCUGUGAGGGGGCUGGAGCAGCCUGGUUAUUUCCUAUCUGUACCAAAGAGGAGUAUGGUGGGAGAGGGAGUGGAGUGCAGUGUGGCUUGGGCCUGGUGCUGGGAACCUGCUAGCUGAGCACUUCCACAAGGGCAUACCCCUGGGGGCAGGGGCUGGGGCUGAGAACUGCAGCCCUGGGUCUUCCCUUAGGGAGGAAGGGCAGAUGAACCCAGCAGGCUUAGGAGGUGGCACUGGGUGAGGACAGCUGGGCAGGGGCUGCAGAGGGAGGUGGAAAUGAACCCUGAGGGCUCCCCCAACUUGCCAUGCCCUGUCCCUUAGUAGAUGAGUUGCUCCUGAUUGGUCAUUGGGUUUGGGUGAGGCCUGGAGGCUUCAGAGGUGAAUUUAUGCUUGGGAAGCCUGAUCCCAAACCUGAAGGGAAGGGACUUGGAUCUCCUUAUAUUGAAUAAGCUGUUUGGAGGAAGGUGUCUGUCUGGGAGGAUGGGGCAGUAAAUGAGGUUGGCAGAGUGGCAGUGGGGGCUCUGCAGAGCCAGCCUUGGAGCCUGCUCAUUCUGGGCCCUUGCUGCCAAGGAGCCCAGCCUCACCUAGCAGGAAAGGAGAUGAAGGCCCUCCUCCCAGGAGGUAGGGUCUUGGCUGCCCCGAACUUAAAUGCUUUUGAAAUCUCUUAGAUGUGGAAAUAUUUUUUCGAACCUGAAAAUGCAGCUGGUAGAAUUUCAAUGGAAGCAUAAUCCAUGUAAAAUAUAUUUUAGUUGAUAUUUUGUAAAAUGCACUUUUUGUGUGUGUUGAUCCUGGUUUCCCAGAUCUGUAUUUCAGUGUUUACAAGGGAGGAAGGACCUUUCCUCACCUCCCUUUUGACAGAGAUUAGAAGUACUUCUUUAAGAAAAAAAUAAAUUUGAGAAAUUGUAUUGAUUUAGAAAAGGA